UCAAGGUAGCAACUGGGAAGUGGAAGCAGAUCAGCAAAUACUGUCCCCUUGAUCUCUACUCAGGAAACAAACAGAGAAUGCACUUUGCCUUGAAGAGUUUGCUGCAGGAGGCACAGAACAACUUGAAGAUAUUUAAGAAUGGUGAGCUGAUUUACGGCUGCAAAGAUGCCCGGAGCCCCGUGGCUGACUGGAGCGAGCUUGCACACCACCUGAAGCCGUUCUUCUUCCCUUCCAACGGCCUGGCCAGUGGGCCCCACUGCACAAGGGCUGUGAUCAGGGAGCUGGUGCACGUGAUCACACGGGUGCUGCUGAGUGGCUCGGACAAGGGCCGGGCAGGCACCCUGAGUCCGGGGCUCGGGCCUCAGGGCCCGCGAGUCUGCGAAGCCAGCCCUUUCAGUAGGAGCCUUCGCUGCCAAGGAAAAAACACCCCAGAGCGCUCGGGGUUACCGAAGGGCUGUCUUCUGUACAAAACCCUCCAGGUGCAGAUGUUGGACCUGCUGGACAUCGAAGGCCUCUACCCUCUGUACAACCGGGUUGAGCGAUACCUGGAAGAGUUUCCCGAGGAGAGAAAAACCUUACAAAUAGAUGGGCCUUAUGAUGAAGCAUUUUACCAGAAGCUGCUUGACCUUUCCACUGAGGAUGACGGGACAGUGGCCUUCGCGCUAACGAAGGUGCAGCAGUACCGCGUCGCCAUGACUGCCAAGGACUGCUCCAUCAUGAUUGCACUGUCUCCCUGUCUGCAGGAUGCCAGCUCUGAUCAAAGGCCUGUCGUCCCUUCAUCGAGGUCCAGGUUUGCCUUUUCCGUGUCUGUGCUGGACCUUGACCUCAAGCCCUACGAGAGCAUUCCCCAUCAGUAUAAACUGGACGGCAAGAUCGUCAACUAUUAUUCAAAGACUGUACGUGCCAAAGACAACGCCGUGAUGUCGACUCGGUUCAAGGAAAGCGAAGAUUGCACAUUAGUUCUCCACAAGGUCUAACUCUUUCCCUGCAGUGUCUUUGAAACUUGAACAUAAUGUGAAGGCUGAAUGAUAGAGAUAUUUUCUGUUGUGUUGGGUGACCUUUGGUUGUGAAUGUUUUUGCUUUUAACCCCUUUUGAGGUGGGAUUGCCUCUUGGAGACAUGGAAUUGAAGAGCACUAGAAACAACUUCCUGGACAAGGAAUGUAGGAAGUGAGUGCUGUGUCCCAGGAAGCUGCUCACACUCUUAAAAUGGAAGUGUCCGUUAAGCCCUGGGAAGACGUUCUGGAUAGUUCUUCUUUCCCAACCAGGGCUCAUGUCUGAUUCUCUAAUGCGAAAAGCCUUAUUCUAAGACCCAAGGUUUGGAUCUGCUACCACCAGACUCCUAACAUAGAAAACUUGAAUUGUCACAUACAUUUUACAGUUUGGACUUUUAAGAAAACAUGGAUACUACUGGAACUUCCCCCAGCUGAGUUACAUGGUCACUUUUUCAGUGCAAGCCACAUAUCAACACAGGUUUUUAGGUGGUUCCCUGCUGCACAGCGUGACCUCGUGGUCGCGCAGAUGCCGAUUCUGAGCAGUGUAGACUCAGGGUCCCUGUGGAGGUGCUGAAGCCCACAGUUCCACACAGGGCAGCAGGGAGCGCAAGGCUCAGGUCAGGAUGGACACCACUCAUGCGAGCAUUGACCUUUUUUUUUUUGCUUUACAAUUUAAUCUUUCACAUGAGGGGGAGAUGAGCUGUUCUUUCCCACUAAAAAUUGCUGCUGUAGAAGUUGGAGGUGGAGCUGUGACUGGCUGAGCUGCUGUGGCCGGGCUGGGCAGUGUGCCCCAACAGCUCAGUGCUUUCCUGACACUCCAGUGUCUGGGGUGGUUGAGGAGCGAGUUCUCUCUUCCUCCCAGACCAAGUUCCUCCCUCGGGUUUGCCUUGAGACGUGUUGCGUUUUUGGGCCCCGUGGCCUCUCCCUGUUAGGCUGCCACAGGCCCUGCUUCUGGAAGGUGAACAGCUCCUGGCUGCUGCCGAGAGGGUUCUCGUUGGGGUCACCAAAGUGUGCCCGGCUGCUAUGAAAAACGUUGGGAAUCUUGGUUUCAGUUUUUUAUUCUAUGCUAGGUUGUACAGACUUAUUUAUAUCAUCGUUUUGAGGGACUAAUGGAGGCUUAUUGUAACAUAUAAUAUUAGUGAAACCAUGGAAUUAUAUGAAAAUGAUACAUGAGAAAUAAGGAAACUAUUUUGCUGAUUGUAAAUUUUUGUGGGAAAUUUUGUGAUAACUUGAGAAUUAUACUUGUUUGAAUCAAGGCAACUCUUCUAGAAUUUAUUGUUCAAUUCUGUCAUAUUUACUUCUAAUUCUACUCUCAGAGGUGCAAAAAGAUACUUAUCUAACUGGACACUUUUACUGUUUUCUUCUCACUUCCAAUGACACCGUCUCAUACACACGGGUCCUGUGUGCUGGGAUGGGGGCUUUGGUGAAGUGCACGGAGCUCACGGACAAGCCGCAGGCUCUGGGAAGCGUGGAGGUAGUGGCCGUUGAGUACUGUCUUGACCCAAGGGAGUUCACUGUUGCUGGGCUGGGGCUGGGGCAGCCUGGUUUGGGAUGAUUUUGCCCAUUGUCACGGUGUGUGGAGGAUGCUGGGUCCUGGGUUCAAGUGCACAUGUGAGGGAACCCCAGUCCGUGGGAAGGUGGGCUGGGCUCCCUAGGUCCUUCAGGGCUGCAAGAGUUAUUGCCUAGCACAGGGCCCAGACAGGGCUGGACUAGACACGAUGAAAACAGCCUGUAUUUGAGGGAGAAGAGAAAACAGAUGGAGACCCCCACUCUGUCUGGUCUUGGCUCCCACCAGCCCGGGCUGUGAGGAGCCCCUGAGCCGCGGGUGCCACUGCUGUGGAUGCGUUUCUGGCCCGUCUUGGAAACUGCUGCUGCUGCGUAGUCAUGACGGCCCUGACUGGUUUGAGACAACACGCGUUCACAGAUCUUAACAAUGCUAAAUGGGCGACUGAUGAGGUCACGGUUCUUAAGGCACAUCCGGGACGAUCGAUAUAGCACUUAGGCUAUGCAGGGGGGUCUUUCUUUCAUAAAGGACCUCAUUCCUUGCGUCCCAGCCCAGGAACAGUGCUGUCUUUGCUGUCUUAGGCCAUUCUUGUUAUUAAGCUGACAGCUUCACUUUCUUGUGGAAGACCAAGAACAGCAUGAGGACUUGCUGAGACUGCCUCACGGUGCCACCAUGCGGACCGGGGGGAGGCAGGGAGUGAGGGUGUGGCUCCCCUGGGCUACUAAGGACAGUUUAAAGAUGAGGCGCCAUAGGCAUCCGUCUCCAGAGCCCCCAGGAGGCAGGAACCAGGAUAAGGGUGGCUUCUCCCAGCUGAGUAAUGUGGCCACCAUGUCCAAGGUGGACUCGGUGUGAGGCUGCAGUGGGUGGGGGAUGGAUCCUCCCCACACAUCUGAGGACACACAACCACUUGGUACAUUUUCUCAGAUGUUAAGCUUAUUUUUAUAAACCACAUUGUACGUGUCACUUUUAUUUGGCAUUUUAUACUUAACUAGUUGUAUUUAUUUUUCAUGUCAUGAGAGUUUCCAUAUAAUGUGCCAUAACUGCAUAGACAGCACGUCUUCAGGGUGUGGUUUCUAAGCAGAAAAUAGCAAAUGUUUAUAUUGAAUAAAAUUGCAUGUUCCUCCACGCA